AGUGGCGGGCCGGGCGCUGGAGUCGGAAGCCUGUGCGCGGCAGCCGCCGCCGAGCCGGCCGGGGCGCACGGAGAGCGCGCGGGACUCGCUGCAGCGGCGGCCGGGUCGCGGCGCACCCGGGCCGGGACCGGAGCCGAGCCUAGCGCGGCGCCCGCGACCCGUCAGCCGCGGCUCCUGCUCCCUCGAUCCCGCGCGGGGAAAGGGCCGGCGGCUGUUGGCGUCGGCGGGGCGCGGAGGAACCGCGGCGGCGGCGGCGGCGGCCGCAUCCUUGCCGCCCGCCCCGGCCCAGCCGCGUCCCGGAGCCGUCGGGCAUGGAGCCGUGGAAGCAGUGCGCGCAGUGGCUCAUCCAUUGCAAGGUGCUGCCCACCAACCACCGGGUGACCUGGGACUCGGCUCAGGUGUUCGACCUUGCGCAGACCCUCCGCGAUGGAGUCCUGCUCUGCCAGCUGCUUAACAACCUCCGGGCGCACUCCAUCAACCUGAAGGAGAUCAACCUGAGGCCGCAGAUGUCCCAGUUUCUCUGUUUGAAGAACAUAAGGACAUUUCUCACGGCCUGUUGUGAGACGUUUGGAAUGAGGAAAAGUGAACUUUUCGAGGCAUUUGACUUGUUUGAUGUUCGUGACUUUGGAAAGGUUAUAGAAACAUUAUCACGACUUUCUCGAACACCUAUAGCAUUGGCCACAGGAAUCAGGCCCUUCCCAACAGAAGAAAGCAUUAAUGAUGAAGACAUCUACAAAGGCCUUCCUGAUUUAAUAGAUGAAACCCUUGUGGAAGAUGAAGAAGAUCUCUAUGACUGUGUUUAUGGGGAAGAUGAAGGUGGAGAAGUCUAUGAGGACUUAAUGAAGGCAGAGGAAGCACAUCAGCCCAAAUGUCCAGAAAAUGAUAUACGAAGUUGUUGUCUAGCAGAAAUUAAGCAGACAGAAGAAAAAUAUACAGAAACUUUGGAGUCAAUAGAAAAGUAUUUCAUGGCACCACUAAAAAGAUUUCUGACAGCAGCAGAAUUUGAUUCAGUAUUCAUCAACAUUCCUGAACUUGUAAAACUUCAUCGGAACCUAAUGCAAGAGAUUCAUGAUUCCAUUGUAAAUAAAAAUGACCAGAACUUGUACCAAGUUUUUAUUAACUACAAGGAAAGAUUGGUUAUUUACGGGCAGUACUGCAGUGGAGUGGAGUCAGCCAUCUCUAGUUUAGACUACAUUUCUAAGACAAAAGAAGAUGUCAAACUGAAAUUAGAGGAAUGUUCCAAAAGAGCAAAUAAUGGGAAAUUUACUCUUCGAGACUUGCUUGUGGUUCCUAUGCAACGUGUUUUAAAGUACCACCUUCUCCUCCAGGAACUGGUCAAACAUACCACUGAUCCGACUGAGAAGGCAAAUCUGAAACUGGCUCUUGAUGCCAUGAAGGACUUGGCACAAUAUGUGAAUGAAGUGAAAAGAGAUAAUGAGACCCUUCGUGAAAUUAAACAGUUUCAGCUAUCUAUAGAGAAUUUGAACCAACCAGUUUUGCUUUUUGGACGACCUCAGGGAGAUGGUGAAAUUCGAAUAACCACUCUAGACAAGCAUACCAAACAAGAAAGGCAUAUCUUCUUAUUUGAUUUGGCAGUGAUCGUAUGUAAGAGAAAAGGUGAUAACUAUGAAAUGAAGGAAAUAAUAGAUCUUCAGCAGUACAAGAUAGCCAAUAAUCCUACAACCGAUAAAGAAAACAAAAAGUGGUCUUAUGGCUUCUACCUCAUCCAUACCCAAGGACAAAAUGGGUUAGAAUUUUAUUGCAAAACAAAAGAUUUAAAGAAGAAAUGGCUAGAACAGUUUGAAAUGGCUUUGUCUAACAUAAGACCAGACUAUGCAGACUCCAAUUUCCACGACUUCAAGAUGCAUACCUUCACUCGAGUCACAUCCUGCAAAGUCUGCCAGAUGCUCCUGAGGGGAACAUUUUAUCAAGGCUAUUUAUGUUUUAAGUGUGGAGCGAGAGCACACAAAGAAUGUUUGGGAAGAGUAGACAAUUGUGGCAGAGUUAAUUCUGGUGAACAAGGGACACUCAAACUACCAGAGAAACGGACCAAUGGACUGCGAAGAACUCCUAAACAGGUGGAUCCAGGUUUACCAAAGAUGCAGGUCAUUAGGAACUAUUCUGGAACACCACCCCCAGCUCUGCAUGAAGGACCCCCUUUACAGCUCCAGGCCGGGGAUACCGUUGAACUUCUGAAAGGAGAUGCACACAGUCUGUUUUGGCAGGGCAGAAAUUUAGCAUCUGGAGAGGUUGGAUUUUUUCCAAGUGAUGCAGUCAAGCCUUGCCCAUGUGUGCCCAAACCAGUAGAUUAUUCUUGCCAACCCUGGUAUGCUGGAGCAAUGGAAAGAUUGCAAGCAGAGACCGAACUUAUUAAUAGGGUAAAUAGUACUUACCUUGUGAGGCACAGGACCAAAGAGUCAGGAGAAUAUGCAAUUAGCAUUAAGUACAAUAAUGAAGCAAAGCACAUCAAGAUUUUAACAAGAGAUGGCUUUUUUCACAUUGCAGAAAAUAGAAAAUUUAAAAGUUUAAUGGAACUUGUGGAGUACUACAAGCAUCAUUCUCUCAAGGAAGGGUUCAGAACCUUAGAUACAACUCUGCAGUUUCCAUACAAGGAGCCAGAACAUUCAGCUGGACAGAGGGGUAAUAGAGCAGGCAACAGCUAAUGAGCUGUGUGCUACAACUAAUCACAAAAGAUUAGCAUGCAAACAAAAGCAUGUUAUGGUUGGACUGUGAGUCUAAGUCGAAAACCUUUUCUCUCAUCGUUUAAUGUUACAUAAUCUUCCUGGAGAUAGAGCAUGUAACAAAAAAAUUGAAAAAUGUCAUCAAGAAGGUGUGAUUUUAUUUUCUUAAUCUGAUAUCACUUUAUUUUUUUUAAAUAAGUGUUUUGGGGAAGAAGUGAAUACAAUUUCAUUACUCUUAGAAUCUUUAGCCUAAGCAACACUGGGAUAUCUAGAGGUAUUUGAAAACAGAAUUUGCGUCGGUUUAAUAUAACUUUAUAUUUUUCCUUGAAAGCAGAAACUGAAAGGGGAACAGGUAAUGCUCUGGGUUUCAACAACAUCAGUGAAGUUUUAUACAUUUCAAUUCAAGUAAACAAACAAUCUGUCACAUCAACUGACAUAUUUUUUAUUUAAGUAACUUAAUAUAUGUUUUCCUCACAGUGAUCAAUGAUGUAUGCCUAAGCUCGUGCAAUGAAAGUAGAGCGAACUUUAUGUUAAAACUUUAAACACCUAUUAGAUUUUAUGGUGUUAUUUUUUAGCCCAAGAUUACCUGAUUAUUUUAGAUUCUCAAAUAGGCAUAAUUUUUGCUCAUUCAAAAAUGGAAGUUUUCUCCAAAAAAACAAUUUUCCUACCAAUAUCUUAAAACUCUGUUGAAGCUAUGACAUUUCCCCCAGCAUGAAACAUGUAAUUUUCGAAGCUCUGUUUCUUUGCCUUCCCAGCAGCAAGAGAUAAUAAAAGUUGCCAGGGAGGUCAGUUAGAUGAAAAAUCCUGUUUGAGUUGUUCACUUAGCUCUAGAGAGCCUAGGAGGGAGAAGUGGGGCAGACAGGGAGAACAGAUGUCCCAUAUUAGGUAGGAAGGUCACUAACCCUCAUAUUUCACUCUGUGGUUCACUCCCAGCCAAUUCCUUAGUGUUUAGUACAUGGAGGUACUCAGAGAAUGUAGCCCGGCAAUGAAUGAAGUUGUCUAACUUAAAAUUAUGUCUCAUGUUUAAUGAAGUAUUUAAUGCUCAACUUGUUUGACAACUAAGAAGGGAAUUACAGGACUUUUUCUUAAAAAAAAGCAUAGCCAGUAGAAUGUCUUUGAAUAUCCAUGCUAGCCCCAGAUAAAUUUUUCAGCAAAUAAACUCAUGAGUUCAAACUUCCCUAUCCAGUCUUUUUAAGAGAUUCUGACAACUUGAAUCAAGCCACUAAAACUUUUUUUUUGUAAUUGUGAAGGGAAAGCAAACAAUUCAUUGAAAAUUUUAUAUUUGUUAUCGUUUGGUUUUGUUCAUCAAUUAUUCAUUCAUUCGUUAAACAGAUAUAUAUUAAACACCUAACACAUACAAGGCACUGUUCUGGUUCUGGGAUAUAGCAAUUAAGAAGACAAAGUUCCUGCCUUUAUGGAGUUUACAUUUCAAUGGGGAAACUCAGGCAAGUCUGGUUUGGAGGAGUUUCAUAUUUUUAUAUAGAGUGGUCAGGUAAGAUCUCCCUCGUAAAGCAACUCAAAAGGAGAGAAGGGGUGUAGGUUGGUAAUGAUUGCACAGUGGUUAACACUCCAAGAUUAGUCAUUCGUUACUGCAAAGAAGGAUUACAAUCUUAGAUCAAAUUUGUGAUACCAUUCCAGUGUUUUAUUUACUUUAUACUAACUUUGUAUAAAGUUAGAGGAAGACUAAGAUGGUUCUGAGGACUAAAUGAGGUGUUCUAUAUAAAGCACUUAGCAUAGUGCUCUUACAUGGUAAACAGUAAAAGUUACUGCUGACUCUACAACUUCUACUUCCUCUACUACUGCUGCUACUUCUAACUCUUAUUCUAACACAGUACUUUCCUAUAUUUCUAAGGCUUGAAUACAUUUACUAAUUAUGACUCAUAGCAAUGUACAUCUUUGCCUUUAUGAUUUUUUAAAUAUAACUUGCUUAUUUUUAUACCAAGUCUUGAUAAAAGCUCACCCUUAAAGAAAGACUGCUUCUAUUUUUAUGCAUUUUAUACAUCCCAGGAAGUGGUAAGGAGGAAAUGCUGCAUGUUUGUAUAGAAAGAUUGUGCAAGAUGUCUUCAUAUUGCUUACCUUUGGUUCAUAGCUUUAGGUAUGCUGCUAUCAUCUAAAAAUAACAUUUGCCAAGCAUUAUUACCUUGGGAUACUGGGUUGGACAGAAAUGGCAUCUCCAUUACUUCUAAAAGUCCUUGGAGGAUACAGAGCAGGCAAGGUAAAGCUUGGAACCAUUCUGUGUUCUGAGUAGAGGUUGAGAAUAGAACUUCAACUCCUGAAACCUGCUGUUUAUUAUUGUUAUUAUUUUUAAAUAAUCUAGUCACCUUGGAAAAGAAAGCCCCAGGGCACUGUAGUGGCCACUUACUUUUGGGCUACUCUAGGUUAGAAUGUUCGUAGAAUGUUUACCAAUUAUUUUUUCAAGUAUGUACAAUGUGAUAAGAUUAUGACAGGACUAUCUUAUGCAAAUUCAAAGUAACAUCUAAAAAGAUAUUGAUUAGAAUUAAGCAAGUGUCCAAAGUAUUGGGCAAGGAGCAUAACAUUUUAAAGUUAGGGGCCCAUUGUAGGCUGUCUCUCAGCCUCUCUCCCAGAGUGAUGGGAUUUUAUCUUUGUCUUUGGAAUGACUUAAGAGCAUUUCUAAGGGAGAAGAAAAGAGAGAAAGAAAAAGAACAAAGAGAGAACUCAGGCAUAGCAGGGAGCUCUUGGGCUUCCUCUAGAAACUUCAGUGACUCCAUGAAAGAUGUUCUAUGGAUCUUUGUAAAAAUCCCAUUAUUUUCCAAAAUGGUCAUCUCAAACCUGCCUUAGAUUGCUUUAGGUUUACCUGUAGGGCUUGUAUAUUUGAAGGGCAUUAAAUUGACUUUUGCAUUUCUUGCUCUACAAUGAACACAUAAUUAUUUUGAGGUCUGCCAGAGUAGCUGUCUGACCUUAGGCGAGUCACUUAGCCUGUCUGGACCUUAGCUUUCUCAUCUGAUGAAUGAGGAAUGAAAUUAGAGAUUUUAUAAUGUUCUUUUAAAAAUAGCAUCUUAGGUUUUUUCCUUUGUUUGCAUGAGAGAAGCAGGUAAGGUAAUGUUAACAGAUUGGUGCAUUAGGAAAAGUUGUAUGUUUAGCUAUUUUGUGACCCAUAAGCAGACCUUAAAUAUUUUGCCAAGUUUUUAUUUGUAGAGAAUUAGUUGGGCCACAGAGUAGAGUUGGGUAAUUUUUUUAAAUGGCUAUCACUAUAUUUAUAUAAUAUCCAAGUAUCUUCUGUAAGAACUUAUUAAUUACAAAAGGGUAAUAGUAAUAACCAAGUGAUUGAAGUUAACAUCCCUAAUAAUGGGACAAAUAAAUAUCAUGUACCUCCUAAUAUAAUGCUCCAAGCAGGACAAACCAACACUUUGGUGGUAUUAUUGUCCCCAAAAAGCAUAAGUGGAAUCUAAUCAUGAGGAAACAUCAGACAAUCCCAAACUAAAAGACAUUCUGCAAAAUAAUUGGUCUAUACUCUAAAACCUUCAGUGUCAUUAAAGAAAAAGUCUGAGGAACUGUUUCAGAUUAAAGGAGACCAAGAGAUGUGACAACUACAUAUAACAUGUGGUCUUGGAUUGAAUCCUAGAACAGGGGUUGGGAAGAUACAUACACACACACACACACACACACGUAUGUAUAUAUAUGUGUGUGUGUAUAGUAACAUAUUUUGUAUAUGUUAUAAAAUAUGUGUGUAUAUAUGUUGCUAUAAAAGAUGUGAUACAAUUGGCAAAUUUUGAAUAAAUUCUCUUGAUUAAAAAAUAGUACCGCAUCAAUGCAAUUUUCUGCUUUUGAUAAUUGUACUGUGGUUAUAUAAGAGAAGAGAAUACCUUUGUUUUUCAGGAACGUGUGCUGAGUAUUUAGCAAUAAGGGGCAUUAUGUCUGCAAUUUAUUCUCAAGUGGCUCAGGAAAAAUACAUAGAUUGAUAAAGCAAACAUCAUAAAAUGUUAACAUUUGGGGAGUCUGAAUGAAAAAUAUGUGGGAAUUCCUUUUGCUCUCCUUGCUACUUUAAGUCUGAAAUAUUUCAGAAUAGAAGUUUUCAGUUGUGGAGAUGAUCCCAUUUGCUGGCUAUAUCUGAAGAAUUGGGAGGUAGUGACAGUGUCCUUCUUUUGCCUGCUUCAGACAUAGAAGCGUCUGGUCCAUUGAUUUCAGGACGUGUGGAACACUAGCAUGUACUGAACAGAUCAUAUUUGAAGCCAUCCGUUCCUUACCUGUGACCUCAUUGGAUUUGCUUCAUUCAUUCAUUCAUUCAUUUAUUCAUUCAUUCAUUCAUUCAUCCCUUUAUCCUGAAAAUAUUUUCAGUACUUAGUAUGUGCUAGGCCUUGUGCUAGAUACUUGAAUUAUAAUAGUGAAUAAGAUACACAAUCUGGUGAACAAGAACAGACAAAAACAAACACCUUCAAUAAUCACAAAUUUUGAUAAUCCUUAUGAAGCUGAAGCAUAAGUGCAAGGAAAUGGGAGCAGGGCCAUUUAGCCUUCAGGGUCAGAGAAGGGCUUUUUGAAGAAGUGACAGUCAGGCUAAACUUAAAGGAUCUACAAGAGCUGACAGGGUGUGGGGUGGUGGCCAAUAGGGAACCUGCAUAGCAAAGAGGUCGUUUGUGUGAAGGUUCAUAAGCAUUAGAGAACUUCAUAUUUUUAAGGAACUGAAAAAGGACCAAUGUGUUGUGAGUAUAGUAAGUGGAUUCUGAUAUUUGCACUAGGAAAGUAUUGAAGUUUUACAGACAGAAAAUGGCAUGAACUAAUUUACAUUGUCUUAAAAGACCACUGACUGUUCCUGAGGAGUGGCCUAGAGGGAGGCAUGCACAGAGGGAAGAUGAGUUAGGAGGCUAUUGCAGAUGUCCGUGAGAGGGAUAAGCAUGCUUUGAACAUGAGUUGCAUAGUGACAGCAGAGAAGGAUAGUGGCAGGUUUGCGUAUAUCUUAGAGGUUGAGUUGAUUGGAUAAAGGAUUUGAAAUCAAAUUAGUACAAGUAUGGUACAUAAGUAUUUGCUUUGGACAACUGGCAAGUGAUAAAACCAUUAACAAUCCAGGAAACAGAAGAGAUAGAACAGAUUUAAGAGAAAAGAGAAUAUAUUCAGUUUUGCACAGUGUUUAGGUACCUGCGGAUAUUCAAUGGUUCAGGAUGCAGCUGGCACUGAGGAGAGUGGUCUGGAUUGAAGGUAGAAUUUUAUGAAUCAUUAAUACUCCAUUUCAUAGUUCACAUAGAAUAUAGUGAUGUGAGAAUUAUAGGCAUUUGUAUAUAGGCUUAAUUUCUUCUGGUGCAUUGUUUGCUGGAGCCCUAGAAGCCAGGACCCUUUGCUUGUCAUUCUCAAUUGUACUUUUGCACAUGCCUUGCAUGAAAUAGCCUCAGAAGGGGCUAAAUAAGAGAAGUCAGAGUCUAAGGUUCACAGGAGACACAGCAGAUAUUAGAGUGCUAAGUUGAAACUGGAAAAGCAUGGGAAUAUGGGUGAGUUUGAAAACAAAGUGUAGAUCAGCAUGUUCCUUUCAGUGUGGUGACAAAUAGUGUAGCAAUUCUUCAAAGAUUGACAAAGGCUACUUUUGUCAUUGGAGCCAUAAGUUUGACCUUGCAGGAAGAAGUAGAAGCCAGAACAGAGCCUAGGCUGUCUCUCCCUGGGUGUGGUCUCUUUCCUGUCACCCACUGUCCCCAUUAUUCUAUUCACCAUCCAACAACAUGCUUAUCCUUCAUUUUUAGUCAGUAUUUUGGGUAGAAACAGAAACUUGGAUAAUUUGUGUCGUAUUUAUUUAACUCAGUAGAACAUAAAGUAGCAUUCUUAUUCCUGAUAAUUCCUUAAACAUCCUAAUAAUUCCUUAACUACUAUUUAUUAGUUAUAUUACAAUAGAAUAGAGACAAUAUUUAUUAUCUCCUUCGUACAGGUUCCUAACCAUCCACUUAACUUAGUUUCUCCCUUGCCCUUUUAAUUCAGCAUUCCCAUAUUCACCUGCCUUUAUUUUCUGAUUUUAUUGUAUCCUCAGUUUUUUUGUCAUCUUUUCCUCGGUCAUUUUGCAAUUGGGUUUGAUAUGAUCUAAUUUUAUUCUGGUAAUUUAAAUAUUUGUUUUAAUCUCAUUAUAUUGGUUUCCUAGUACUGCUAUAAAAUUAUCACGAACCAAGUGGCUUAAAACAACAGAAGUUUACUCUCUCACCCUUCUGGAGGCCAGAAGUUGAAAACCAAAGUGUUAGCAGGGCUAAUUCUUCCUGGAGGCUCUGAGGGAGAAUCCCUCCCAUGCCCCUCUCCCAGUUUCUACUGGCAAUCCUUGGCAUGGCUUGGUUUAUAGAUGCACCGCUCCAGUCUCUGCUGGUCUUCACGUCACCUUCUGUGUGUAUCAUUGUCCCUUCUUUUCUCUUAUGGACACCUGUCAUUGGAUUUAGGGCCCACCCAAAUACAGCUUGAUCUCAUUAUGAGAUCCUUAACUGAAUUACAUCUGCAAAGACCCCUGUUUCAAAUAAAGUCACAUUCACAGGUUCACAGGUCCUGGGUGGGCAUAUCUUUUUGAAGGGCCACCAUUCGACCCACUGCAGUUCCACUGUAUUAAUUUUAAACUUUUCUCUAAAAUUUUCCAUCCUUAUUCUAAUUUUUCUUUUUGUCAUUUUGUAACUUGGAGUUAUAAGAGGACUUUACAUUAUUACAGCAGUCAGGCAGUCAGUGAAUGAGAUUUAUACAAGAAAAACACUACUUUAAUACAAAAAAAAAGUGUUUUCAAUGAAUUGUAUUGCCUUUCCAUGGUGAAAUGCCUUAUCUUUCUGAGAGACUGCACUUCUAGCCAAUGCAGGCUCCUAAACAAUACUUGAAUGACCAUUUGUCUGAAACAUUGUAUUAAAUAUUUUAUAUGGAAUAAGAGAACCUAAGAAUUCUGAAAUUCAAUAAUUUGAUGAUUAACAGGACACUCUUACUUUUCAAACCCCUUUUACAAAUAUCAGAUCAAUAUCUCCAAUGGAGUAUUCCAGGAAUCUCUAGCCCUGUGAGAAGUACCAUGAAAAGAUUUCUUUUGUCAAACAGAUAUAUAAGAAAUGCUGCUAGUAUGAUGUAUUCCCUUCUAGGAAAGUGACAGUUUAUCUAGAGUUUUCCCCAGUUUAUUUCAUCAUGCAACACUGUCUCAUAGUGUUUAAUGCUCAUGUUAGGAGGCUUAAAAGAGUUAGUAGGUGUGAAAUACUGAGAAUAGCAUCUCACAUGUGGGAAGUGCUAUGUGUUUUGCUCCUGCUAUUACUACUGCUGCUCCUGCUACCACUUCCAAUACUGGUACCCAGUGUGAAGUGUUACAUUAGCCUCAUUUGACAAUUUUAAGUAUAUUUAUAAAGUCCUUCUCCUUUUCCCUGAUACUUUGGUUUCCUACUUCUAUUUCCUGGAUACACACUAUUCCGGUAUACACACUAUUCUAUGGACUAAGUUAGUUAUAACAUAUUGCUGACAUUUUUAUAUUCUUCUCUCUUCAUUUAUGAUGUCCACAUAAUUUACAGUUCUUGAACAACUGAUCAACUGCAAUUGCACAUCUUCAUUAGUAAGUGAUGCUGGGCUUCCCUUUUUUAUUUAGUUACUUCAGGAUCUUUACCAGCUACUCUAAAGCAUUUUUAUUCUGAGCCUGAUGGCUUUAAAAGUUAGCAACCAGUAUCCAGGAUCCCUUCAGAAUAUGGCUUGCAGGUGUAAAUUCUACAGAUUCAGAUAACCUCAUUCAGUGCUAUCUUUUAAAUGUUUCAAGGCUCAGAGCAGUACUUAUGAUCUUAGAAUUUCUCAUCUUUUAUACUGUUCAUUAAUACUUUUAUAGUGUCUCAUAUAACCUCAUGUUCUAAAUUGAAAACUGGUCUCGGCCAGGCAGAGUGGCUCAUGCCUGUAAUCCCCAGCACUUUGAGAGGCUGAAGCAGGUGGAUCAUUUGAGGUUAGGAGUUUGAAACCUGCCUGGCCAACGUGGUGAAACCCCGUCUCUACUAAGAAUACAAAAAAUUAGCCCGGUGUGGUGGCACGCAUCUGUAAUCCCAGCUACUCGGGAGGCCGAGGCAGAAGAAUUGCUUGAACCCAGGAAGUGGAGGUUGUAGUGAGCCAAGAUGGUGCCACUGCACUCCAGCAUGGGCAACAGAGGGAGACUCAAUAUAAAAAAUAACUACAUACAUAGAUACAUGCAUACAUACAUACAUACAAACAUACAUACAUAACUGGUCUCAAUGCAGUUAAUUUACCAUAGUGCUUUCAUAUAACAGCCCUGAUCCAAGAAUUUGGUUUUACUAGUCUCUUGCUUGAAAAACAAACAAAUUCAUCUAAAUGGGGAGAAAUUCCCAGUUUUUCUUCCUAAAAAUUUAACCAGGCUCCUAGUUAUGAGGAUCAAUGCUGAUAUCUCUUUUUUCCUGAUAUAUGACUGAUAUUUGAUUUUCCCUGCUGAAUCCCAAAUCUGCAUAAGGUAGCAGGUUUUAACUCUGCAGCUCUCUUGCUCUUAAUAACAUUAAUAAGCUGACUACAUAUUCGGCUAGGGUUUCCUUUCAUUAAGUUAUACUUUCAUUCAUUGCUUCGUGCAUUCAACAUUUGUUGAGCCUCUGCUUGCAUUAAAUACUAUAUCAUACUCACGUCUCAAGUGUUACAUACAAUACAGCUUAACAUCUAAACAAUAGGUAGGAAUGCCAGAGAAACUCUUCUUGUAUCUAGGCACUUCAAACUUACCAUCCCCAUUAGCCCUAAUACAAGUUUUUUUAAACGUUCUGUAACACUCCUGAGAAGUCAUCAUCAGGCUUUGCUUGAACACUCAAGGGACUUUAUGUUCAAUACCACACAAAACACCCUAUUUUCUGAACAAAUUAAGUUUUUUUCUUUUAUUGAUCUAGAAAUUUGAUGUACUAUAGCUAUUUACUGUGAUUAGUUCAAAAUAAAUAUAUAUUCUUCCUACCAAGAUAACCCCAAAUAUACUAUAAAAAUAAUGCAUUGUACAUUCAAAAUAAAUAUACUAUAUACUCUCCCUCUCAUGGUAACUUUUCAUCUGGUAUGUUCUUUCCCCUUCCCCAUGCUUCCUUCCUACCUCUUCAUUCCUUCCUUUUCUUUUUCAAAAUAAUUAAUCAAUUCCUCAUCAUGUAAAUGGUUGUCAAUUUCCCACCAUCUUCACCACCCUCUGAUAGAUGCACUCCAAUUUGUCAGACCGGGCACAAAAAUUUCAAUAUUGCCUGACUGAUUGGCUCAGAUUUUUCUUUAUUCAAAACUCAUUCUUCAACAGUUAAUUUCCACCCUUCCCUUUCUCCUUCCUCCUCAAAGGGUACAGUUCUACAUAUUUCAGUCGAAUCCAAGCACUUCUUUCCUCAUUUACUGUUUAGUUGUUGCAUCUUCACCAUUAACCUCCUCCAUAGUUCCCCACAUUCAUUCAUUCAUUAUUCAUUAAUGCAUUCAUUCAACAGAUCUUAAUUGAGAGCCUACUUCAGGGCAGGCACUGUUAAAAUACAGCAGUGAAUAGCAUGGAUAAAAUUCCCUACUCUAAUGGAGAUGCCACUUGCUAGUAGGGAAGGUAGCUAAUGGAUUUAGAAAAAUAAUUAAGUGUAUUAUGUUAGACGUUACUGAGCGCUCUGGGAAAAAAAAAAAAAAAAAACUAUGCCAAGGGAGUGGUACUCAUGAGCGCUGAGGGAUGGCUUACAAUUUUUAACUGGGCUGGUUGGGUGAUGAAAAACAAAACUAUAGUCUCAUUUUCCCUCUUUCUGGUAGCGUAGCAGAAAGCUGGUUCAUCACUUCUGAGUUAGUUCAAUGGUAGAGCAGGCUGACACCAGCCACUGGCUCUAGAAGCACUUCUUUCUAACAGGCCACUUGUGUGACCAGGGAGCUUCUGCUAUUAUAAGUUUGCAUAAAUAUCCUGUCAAUACAUAGAGCAGGAUGCUGAAACUGUAACUACAGUGUGUGUAGAGCAUUUGUGCCUCACCUCAGCAGUAGGACAAUGGGAGUUUGGGAGAUUGCAUGCACGCUACCUACUUCUCUGAUUGUGUGUUGUUCCCACAAUAAGCUCUGUUUCUGUCACCAUCACAUGGCACUAGUGGUGUGGAUCCAUGACUUUUAUAGGACAUCACAGCAGGUUUCAUUGUGAAGGUUGCAUUUGAAUCAAGACUCUCAAGGAGGUGAAAGAGAGAACUGUCAGUGCUAAGGGAGGGGUAUGUCUGACUGGGCAAUGUGGCCAGAGCAGAAGGACCAAGAGGAAGAGUAGCUGGAGAUGAGGUUCAAGGGGUAAGUGAGGCCAGAUCACUUAAGGCCCUAAAGGACUUUAGCUUUUACCCUUGAAGAAACAGGAAACCAUUGGAGGGAUGUGGGCAAAGGAGAAACAUGGUCUGUCUUUAAAGUUUUAAUAGGAUUAUUCUAGUUUCUGUAUUAUAAUAAAAAAAACCAUGAAAAUAGAUGACAGAGUAGGCACAGGAAGACCAGUUAGGCCCAUACAGCAAUCAAGGUAAGAGAUGAUAGUGGCCUGGAACAGCACGUAGCCAUAUAGGUGACUAUAUUUAUAUUUUGAGGGUGAUCCAAAAGGAUAUUAUGACACAUCAGAUGUGAUGUAUAAUAGUAAUAGAAGACUUAAGAAUAAUUCUAAGGUUUUUGCUCUGAGCAACUGGGAGUUUGGAAGGUUUUGUUUUGUGUUGAGGGCUCCAAUAGAGCCUAAAGUCUAAUCAUAGCAUUCUCAAUCCAAAAUCAAUCAUUUCCAUAUCUCUACAUAAUUUCUGUCUGUGUCUAUCUCUUCACUAAUUUCUAAGCUCCUGUGAUGUCAGAGGCUGUACCUAUUCAUUAUAUCUCCUAUGAUAUCUUAGCAGUCUUUGGCACAUUAGCAAUAUAAUACAUGUCUGCCAAAUAUUUUUUAAAUAUAGAUUUAGAAUUAACAUCUUGAUAAGCCAUAUGCAUAUAAAUAAUCUGAAAUCCCUAGGCAGUUUUCCAUAGCAAUAAGAAAGACCUUAUACUUAGUUUGUUUUCUUGUUAAUGGCUUUAUAUGUUUAUACUCUGUAGCAUUGAAUACUAAGUAGUAGUUUAUUUUUUACAAUAAUCCUAGACAUAAGUUUUCCUUGUUACAGCUUUGGACUUUGGGUUAACAGAAAUUUGUCUACUUACCAGAUGUCAGCAUUCAAUUAAAUGAAAUUAAUCUAAAUUAUUCCUAGUUUUUUUUCAGUGACAAUAUAUAAAAUAUACAAUAAGCUUUUUUCUUGUAAAUUUGUUUGAGUUCAUUGUAGAUUCUGGAUAUUAGCCCUUUGUCAGAUGAGUAGGUUGUGAAAAUUUUCUCCCAUUUUGUGGGUUGCCUGUUCACUCUGAUGGUAGUUUCUUUUGCCGUGCAGAAGCUCUUUAGUUUAAUUAGGUCCCAUUUGUCAAUUUUGGCUUUUGUUGCCAUUGCUUUGGUGUUUUAGACAUGAAGUCCUUGCCCAUGCCUAUGUCCUGAAUGGUAAUGCCUAGGUUUUCUUCUAGGGCUUUUAUGGUUUUAGGUCUAAUGUUUAAGUCUUUAAUCCAUCUUGAAUUGAUUCUUGUAUAAGGUGUAAGGAAGGGAUCCAGUUUCAGCUUUCUACAUAUGGCUAGCCAGUUUUCCCAGCACCAUUUAUUAAAUAGGGAAUCCUUUCCCCAUUGCUUGUUUUUUGUCAGGUUUGUCAAAGAUCAGAUAGUUGUAGAUAUGCGGUGUUAUUUCUGAGGGCUCUGUUCUGUUCCUUUGAUCUAUAUCUCUGUUUUGGUACCAGUACCAUGCUGUUUUGGUUACUGUAGCCUUGUAGUAUAGUUUGAAGUCAGGUAGCAUGAUGCCUCCAGCUUUGUUCUUUUGGCUUAGGAUUGACUUGGCGAUGCGGGCUCUUUUUUGGUUCCAUAUGAACUUUAAAGUAGUUUUUUCCAAUUCUGUGAAGAAAGUCAUUGGUAGCUUGAUGGGGAUGGCAUUUGAAUCUAUAAAUUACCUUGGGCAGUAUGGCCAUUUUCGCGAUAUUGAUUCUUCCUACCCAUGAACAUGGAAUGUUCUUCCAUUUGUUUGUAUCCUCUUUUAUUUCAUUGAGCAGUGGUUUGUAGUUCUCCUUGAAGAGGUCCUUCACAUCCCUUGUAAGUUGGAUUCCUAGGUAUUUUAUUCUCUUUGAAGCAAUUGUGAAUGGGAGUUCACUCAUGAUUUGGCUCUCUGUCUGUUAUUGGUAUAUAAGAAUGCUUGUGAUUUUUGUACAUUGAUUUUGUAUCCUGAGACUUUGCUGAAGUUGCUUAUCAGCUUAAGGAGAUUUUGGGCUGAGACAGUGGGGUUUUCUAGAUAUACAAUCAUGUCAUCUGCAAACAGGGACAAUUUGACUUCCUCUUUUCCUAACUGAAUACCCUUUAUUUCCUUCUCCUGCCUAAUUGCCCUGGCCAGAACUUCCAACACUAUGUUGAAUAGGAGUGGUGAGAGAGGGCAUCCUUGUCUUGUGCCAGUUUGCAAAGGGAAUGCUUCCAGUUUUUUCGCAUUCAGUAUGAUCUUGGCUGUGGGUUUGUCACAGAUAGCUCUUACUCAAACAACCCCAUCAAAAAGUGGGCAAAGGACAUGAACAGACACUUCUCAAAAGAAGACAUUUAUGCAGCCAAAAAACACAUGAAAAAAUGCUCACCAUCACUGGCCAUCAGAGAAAUGCAAAUCAAAACCACAGUGAGAUACCAUCUCACACCAGUUAGAAUGGGAAUCAUUAAAAAGUCAGGAAACACCAGGUGCUGGAGAGGAUGUGGAGAAAUAGGAACACUUUUACGCUGUUGGUGGGACUGUAAACUAGUUCAACCAUUGUGGAAGUCAGUGUGGCAAUUCCUCAGGGAUCUAGAACUAGAAAUACCAUUUGACCCAGCCAUCCCAUUACUGGGUAUAUACCCAAAGGACUAUAAAUCAUGCUGCUAUAAAGACACAUGCACACGUAUGUUUAUUGCAUCACUAUUCACAAUAGCAAAGACUUGGAACCAACCCAAAUGUCCAACAAUGAUAGACUGGAUUAAGAAAAUGUGGCAGAUAUUCACCAUGGAAUACUAUGCAGCCAUAAAAAAUGAUGAGUUCAUGUCCUUUGUAGGGACAUGGAUGAAAUUGGAAAUCAUCAUUCUCAGUAAACUAUCGCGAGAACAAAAAACCAAACACCACAUAUUCUCACUCAUAGGUGGGAAUCGAACAAUGAGAACACAUGGACACAGGAAGGGGAACAUCACACCCUGGGGACUGUUGUGGGGUGGGGGGAGGGGGGAGGGAUAGCAUUGGGAGAUAUACCUAAUGCUAGAUGACGAGUUAGUGGGUGCAGCGCACCAGCGUGGCACAUGUAUACAUAUGUAACUAACCUGCACAUUGUGCACACGUACCCUAAAACUUAAAGUAUAAUAAUAAAAAAUAUAUAUAUACAAUAAGCAGUAAACAAUAGGGUUUUAGGUCAUUUUGUUUGGGAGAGAUUGGGGAGCAGAUAGUUGAUACUCUGUCUAUGAAUUUUGCAGGGCAUCUAAAACGAUAUGCCUGAGUUCUAAAAUAAAACCAGGGUAAGGAUCACAAAUUUAAAUUAAGCAUUCAUUAAAUUCUCAGCAUGUUCUCUGGUGUUAGGCCAUCUGUAGACAAUCUUGGCAAAACGAACCUCCUAGACUGCUCAUCAAAGCAUCCCACUUAGGAGUACAGUUCUUCAGCAAAACAUCUAGGGCCACUGCUGGGCAGCAAACGCAAGUGAUCAGUGUUGACAGUACCAUUGACCCAAUCUUCUCAUAUUCUUACUAACAACUUUUUGUUACCUGAGUGAGAACACAUGUGCUUGUUACAACUAAAAACUGAGUGUUAAGGAAUGUCUGUCCCAGAGAAUACUUAGCAAGCAACUUAGGGUAAUGUUCUCUGAUACAUGUAAAGGAUAAUUAUUAGUUCAAAAAUACUUAGGAUUUGAUAACUAGUACCUGAACGAAGAGUGUCGAUUAGGUUGGUUUCCAAUGUGUAAAAAUUUCAAAUAUUACUGAAAACUGAGUAAAUUUUCAUCUGCUCAUGAACAUUAAUAGCACGAUCAAGGCAGAACAUAAUACUUUAAAACAAUCCUUAGCCUUGGCAACAAAAGUAUAGGCAUCAAAUAUCCAGUCACUAGUACUUUUUUAUCCUACCAUAAACACUGUGUUCUUUUUCUUUUUAAUUGGCAUUCUUCUGUGUUUUGUGGUGUUAUCUUCUCAGUCAGGUCUCAGAACUGAAUAAUAACCACUAAUGAUUUGCCAGUCAGUUAUUAUGGCUAUGCUGAUAACUUCUAUUCCAAGUUUAUUUAUUUAACAGAUAACUUCUAUUUAUAUUAGGUAAUGUUAGUACUUCAGGUUUUGCUUAACUUGGAAAACUUGAUAAAUAAUAUUUGACUGUGCUCUUAAUAGUUCCUAAUUGGAAACUUUAAGUCACUAAAUUAUGAGCCACUGAGUCAUUUGCUAAUAAUGCCCCAUGUAUGUUAGCUCAGUUGAGAGCCAGGUGUCAUACACAUGCAAAAUAACCAGAUACCUACCUAAGUGUGAUGGUCUCUCUAAGCAAGGUGGCCUCCCUUGCCUAUGCUAAUAUGGAGUUGAAAGUGUUUGUAAAAGGGGGAAAGUUAUGCCGUUAAACGAAGCAUCCAGUUUGCAAAUGAUUACCUAUUGAAAAAGGUCGCAGUAUUGGUGUAAUAUUAUCUAAGUGGAUGCUAAUAUGCAUAAAAGAGUUCUCUUUCAAGAAGCUUCCAGAACAACAUGAUGCAGGUAGGUUGUCUAUAAUGUUAGGCAGUGAAUGAAGAGUCCGGGAGAUGAUAACCACCUCAACGUUCCCAUUUAAAUGUCACUGUUACUGGGCCCUUUUUAAUUCUAUUCCAGGACGUGUACCUACCAAUAAUUUUUACUUUAGAAGUUUCUUGGUGUGGUAGGAGGAGUUUGAUGAUGAAACCAUGCAUCCAUAUAUAUAGAAACAAGUGGAUAUAUUAUCAGUAUGGAUGGAAAUAUAUUUUACAGGUUAAAUCAUUCUAAAAAUAUUUUUAUCAAAUACCUUAUUCUGAUAUUGCUUACAUCUGGGUUUAAAUCCAUACUUUCCUGGAGAAACAUGUUAUCUUUUACUCUUGUCUCAGUAGGUGCCAGGCAUUCAAAUGCUGUUUUUCCAGCUCAAAGGAAUUAAGGACCCAAAGGCAUUUACCAUUGAUAUAUAGGAAGAGUGGCAACAAUAAGUCACGCUACAGUGUGUAGAAAAGUAGAAAGCAUCCCUACCAAUCCUUAAAAUGUUUGGCUGAGAGCUAUACACUGGGUGGCAGGAGAAACUGAUUAACCUUUUACUCCUAAGAAGAUUCCUCAGGCAUAGAGUAUGGUUAAUGCCGUGAGACAUACAGUAUUUAAUAGGUGUUCAGCAUCUCAGAAAAAAAAAAUAAUAGUUAUUUUAGGAAUAUCACUGAUAGAUGGUGGUGCUCAGGAAGCCUGCGGAAUAGAACCCGAAUAUAUUUCGCUUUCUUUGCUUGGUGUUUUGCUGGCCUUUGUUGGAAGUCUUAUGGAGCAGUUUAAGUGAGCAGAAGAUGAGCUAAAGGAAUGGAAGGAGGAGACAUAAGGAACUUGCAGAAUUAAAUACCCUGCCGAGAUACUUGUCCAUUCAGCAGCUUCAGUUGCUUAGCACUGGACCUGAUCCUGUGGAGGAUGCAGAAGCAAUAUUAGAACUGGCCCCUGCCCUCCAGAAUCGCUGUCUAAUUGGGGAUACAACACAGAACGUACAGUAAUUAAAUAUCAGAGCCAUGAAGUGCCAUGAUGCAAUGCCUACCAGAGGGCUAGGAAAGGUCAAAGAAGGGGCCAGAGUGUUGUCUGGAUUGUCAGGGAAGGCUCCUGGGAGGGGUCUGGGCUGGACUUUUGAGACAGGGAAGUUAAGGUCAGCAGAGGUCGGGGAAGGAGCAGCAUUCCAGAAUGAGCAGAUAUUUGGAGUUGGAAAUGUAGCUGAGGGCCUCAGGAGGUAGUAGGAAGCUGGUCUGGGUAAAGAGAACACAUGUGGAAAUGGAUGCAGAUUUCAUUAGAGAGACAAGAGUGGCCAGAUUAUGAAUUGUCAUGGAAUUCAGGCCAAGGGUUUGGAUUUCAUAAUUUAGCAAAUAGCAUGAUAGACUUUACAUCAAAGGUGAGCUGCUGUGAGGCAGUAUUUAGAACAGAAGAGAAAGAAAGCCAGAAGCAAGAAGACCAUUUGGCUGGCAGUUUUCUGAGAGUAGGAAUGAUAUAGAUACCUGAAUUGGGAUGGUGCAGCUGAGAAUUACUGAACGAUUAACUUCAUAUUGCAGAGAAAGAAAGCACUUUACUUAGAAAGGCGACAAGGAGGGCUGAACGGUGUACUAACUUUGCAAGGCUAGUUCACAGAGAGAACAGGAGAGUUCUUGCAGGGGGGAAACAUGGGACUUUGAGCUAGAUUACAGGGAAUAAGUUGAGGAAUUUGGUUUCAGACACAUUAAAUCAGACAUAAAAGCUAGUCUUCAUAGCAGUGUCAUGAAAACAUUUGAAGCCAUAGUCUGAAAUUCAGGUGAGAAGCCAAACCAUAUCGAAGAAUCUCCUGCAUUCAUAAGGGAAAAACAUUAGUUUAAGUGAAGACAGCAGCGGGGCCAAAGCCUAACUGUGAGGGCUAACUACUGUUUGGGUGGAAUUAUAAUAUUUUAGAUAAGAUUUAAGAGGAUUCUAAUUCUAGCUACUUGAUAGGAAUGCGAAUGAUGAUAAGGCUUUUAGAGUUAGAUAAGAGAGAGGGCUAGCACCCUGAUAUUCUGUAAUUGAAACAGAGUUUCAAGUCCUUUGGUCAAGUAUUACCCUUAUUCCUUCAGGAAUAGUAGAUAUUUUAAGAUUACAGAUAGGUUAUCUUAUCUAAUUUACCUACCUAUUGUUGAAAUUAUUUAAUUUGCAUUUAACUGUGUUUUCACUGGCUUAUCAUUUCUCUCUUCUAGAGCUAACUUAUCUCUUGUUAUAUUCCAGACUCUUGGUGUAAAUUACCUUCAUUGAAAAUUUUGGAGAAAUAUAGUGUUUUAUUUCUUUAUGGAUAAAAUAGUCCCAGAGAGAGAGACACAAGGAUGGACACUUAGAAAACAGUCCCAGCUACUCGGGAGGCUGAGGCAGGAGAAUGGCGUGAACCCGGGAGGCGGAGCUUGCAGUGAGCCGAGAUCGUGUAACUGCACUCCAAACUGGGCAACAGAGCGAAACUCCGUCUCAAAAAAAAGAAAGAAAGAAAACAGUCCAAGGAGAGAAUUCUAAUGCCUGACAGAAGUAAUGUUUAGAAUGAGGGCUUCUAACUGAAGUUUUCACAGACAUAGGAUAGAAAUCUUAGCACCAGAUUUUCUGCCAAUAAUAGAGUUAGAUGUGUGUCAUUUGCUCAUUAAAAUGGAGGUGGCAUCCUGUCCUCUAAAAUUAUAUCAUGAUCUCAAGAAAAUGAAAAUGUACCAUUUCUACUGCAUGGCUGAAAAUGAUUUGGGCUGAUUAUAAAAAUUAGUUGUAAUGGCAUGUAUCAGUAUACUUAAAAAUAAAAAAUGUACUGCAGAAUGUG